AGAGGCUCCCCAGCGUCGCCCUAGGCUGGGACUCUAGUAGGUCUUCGGCUCAGUUUUGGCUGCAGCGCCCGCGUAGAUCGCUUCGGCCGGGUUCUACGCCCGGCUCAACUAUGAGCCGGUGCGCCCAGGCGGCGGAAGUGGCGGCCACAGUGCCAGGUGCCGGCGUCGGGAACGUGGGGCUGCGGCCGCCCAUGGUGCCCCGUCAGGCGUCCUUCUUCCCGCCGCCGGUGCCGAACCCCUUCGUGCAGCAGACGCAGAUCGGCUCCGCGAGGCGGGUCCAGAUUGUCCUUCUUGGGAUUAUCUUGCUUCCAAUUCGUGUCUUAUUGGUUGCGUUAAUUUUAUUACUUGCAUGGCCAUUUGCUGCAAUUUCAACAGUAUGCUGUCCUGAAAAGCUGACCCACCCAAUAACUGGUUGGAGGAGGAAAAUUACUCAAACAGCUUUGAAAUUUCUGGGUCGUGCUAUGUUCUUUUCAAUGGGAUUUAUAGUUGCUGUAAAAGGAAAGAUUGCAAGUCCUUUGGAAGCACCAGUUUUUGUUGCUGCCCCUCAUUCAACAUUCUUUGAUGGAAUUGCCUGUGUUGUAGCUGGGUUACCUUCUAUGGUAUCUCGAAAUGAGAAUGCACAAGUCCCUCUGAUUGGCAGACUGUUACGGGCUGUGCAACCAGUUUUGGUGUCCCGUGUAGAUCCGGAUUCCCGAAAAAACACAAUAAAUGAAAUAAUAAAGCGAACAACAUCAGGAGGAGAAUGGCCCCAGAUACUAGUUUUCCCAGAAGGUACUUGUACUAAUCGUUCCUGUUUGAUUACUUUUAAACCAGGAGCCUUCAUUCCAGGAGUUCCAGUGCAGCCAGUCCUCCUCAGAUACCCAAACAAGCUGGAUACUGUGACCUGGACAUGGCAAGGAUAUACAUUCAUUCAGCUUUGUAUGCUUACUUUCUGCCAGCUCUUCACAAAGGUAGAAGUUGAGUUUAUGCCAGUUCAAGUACCAAAUGAUGAAGAAAAAAAUGAUCCUGUCCUUUUUGCCAAUAAAGUCCGGAAUUUAAUGGCAGAAGCUCUGGGAAUACCAGUAACAGAUCAUACCUAUGAAGACUGCAGAUUGAUGAUUUCAGCAGGACAGCUAACAUUGCCUAUGGAAGCUGGGCUGGUGGAAUUUACUAAAAUUAGCCGAAAAUUGAAAUUAGAUUGGGAUGGUGUUCGUAAGCAUUUGGAUGAAUAUGCAUCUAUUGCGAGUUCCUCAAAAGGAGGAAGAAUUGGAAUUGAAGAAUUCGCCAAGUAUUUAAAGUUGCCUGUUUCAGAUGUCUUGAGACAACUUUUUGCACUCUUUGACAGGAACCAUGAUGGCAGCAUUGACUUCCGAGAGUAUGUGAUUGGCCUGGCUGUCUUGUGCAACCCUUCCAACACAGAGGAGAUCAUCCAGGUGGCAUUUAAGCUGUUUGACGUUGAUGAGGAUGGCUACAUAACGGAGGAAGAGUUCUCCACCAUUCUACAGGCUUCCCUUGGAGUGCCUGACCUUGAUGUUUCUGGUCUCUUCAAGGAAAUAGCCCAAGGGGACUCAAUUUCCUAUGAGGAAUUUAAAAGUUUUGCCUUAAAGCAUCCAGAAUAUGCUAAGAUAUUUACAACAUACCUAGACCUCCAGACGUGCCAUGUGUUUUCAUUACCAAAAGAAGUCCAGACAACCCCCUCCACCGCCAGUAAUAAAGUCAGCCCUGAAAAGCAUGAAGAGAGUACCUCAGACAAAAAAGAUGACUGAAAGCAGUAUUUCCAAUAAGGAAAACACAGUAGCUUUUGCUUGAAAUUGUAAAGGCACUUAUUGAUAAUACUUUUAAUGUGUUGGUAAUGAUGUUUAAAAUUGAAAGAUUUUUAAAACAAAAAUGAUAGAUUUUCUUACUAAAAAUGUUUUUAUUAACCUUGCUUUUAUUGGAAAAAAUCAAGCAAUAUUUCGUUUUCUUUUGUGUUAUAUUGUACUUUACUGAUUCAUUUACUGGUGAUACAUAUGUUUUUAUGGAUUUUCCAGUUUAAUUUGCAUAUACAAAUGAAUGCAAUGGUCUAUUGGUGAGCAUUGAGCAACACUGUAUAAAGUUUUAAAAAUGUAAACACUUUUUAAUCUACUUUCCUCUAAAAAUCAAUAAUAUUCUAUUAUUUCUAAUCCUUUUCCACUUGGGAAAUAACAAUGAAGAAUCUGAGAAUUUGACAUCUAUAACUUUACAGAUUCAUUUUUCCAUUUAAAUUUCAGUUUCUUGGAUCACUGAAUAUGGGAAGGGAGAGCUUCACUAAUUAGACGCAGCUUCUUAAGAACUUAUAUUCUCUUUGACAUACAUCUCUAUUGUAGUUUUUUGUUUUGUUUUGUUUUUUGAGAUGGAGUCUUGCUCUGUCACCCAGGCUGGAGUGCAGUGGUGCAAUCUCAGCUCACUGCAACCUCUGCCUCCUGGGUUCAAGUGAUUCUCGUACCUCAGACUCCCGAGUAGUUGGGAUUACAGGUGCCCACCACCACACCCGACUAAUUUUUGUAUUUUUAGUAGCCAUGUGGUUUUGCCAUGUUGGCCAGGCUGGUUUCGAACUCCUGACCUCAGGUGAUCCACCCACCUCAGCCUCCCAAAGUGCUGGGAUUACAGGUGUGAGCCACCGUUCCCGGCCUAUUGUAGAUUUUCUUAACUACUUGCUAAGGAAAUCAUAUCCUUUUACAUGAACUACAGGUUUAGAACUUGGUUUUAAGACAACUGCUAUGGCCAGAAGGUAAAUGGGAAUUGCCUUAUUGAAGGUAACAUUGAUUGCCUAAUAAGAAAAUGAAUUGUUUGCCACAGAGUUGAAUUUAAUUUGAGUUAGAUAGUUCAGAAUGUAGCACUUGCCCUAUAAAUGAAUCAGAUUUGUUCUAUUUAUAUAAUAUUAGAAUUAAUAUAUUAUCAUGUAAGUGGGAAUUUUAUUUUGUUAAGUGGACUCUCAAAUUUUAGAACUUGUGUGAAAUAUCUCCCAGAAAACACAAAAGGUUUCAAGGUAUCACCCAAAGCUAGGGAAUCAACAAACGUACUUUAUUAAUGCAAGACCACAAUUUAAGCCCCAGGCAGGAAUCCAACAGUAACAUUUUUCCUUUAGGUUAAGCAGUAAUUUUUUUGAAUUGUCAUUUUUAAUGGGUCUCACACAUGCAUAUUGCUAAUAUCAUUCAUGUUUGAGGUUUUCAACAAAGAACCAAUUUAUUAAUAUAAUGUACAAAAAUAGUUGGUUCAUUUUCUGAAUUCAGUCUUUGAAAUAAAACUCCUUGUUUUGGCCGUGUUUCUGAAUGUAUUGGUGAUUCACCCCCAAGCUAAUUUUUUAAAGUCAUUUUUGAAGUUGGGAAGUCUCAUGAGAGAUGUUGAAGUAUGUAUUUAAUCAAGAGUCAUGAUUUCAAACUAGUUUUACAUAUUAAGCAGUUAGUGUUCUAAUUUAAUGGGUAAAUGUGUGUUUGGAUAAAUAUCUGAAAAUUUUAUCCUUAAGUAUAUAUAAUUAUUUGCCUCUUAUAUGUCUUAAAGCUAUUUAAACAAGGUGUUAAAUGAGCCAAAACAAUUAAGUAAUUAGAACAGUACAUUUUUAUCAGAGUGUCUGUCAUAUGCAAUGAAUGUAUGUAAUACUAAAAAAUCAUGACUACUUUUAUCAAAGAAAAACCACACAUUAAUCCUAUUAAUCAUGAAAGCGUAGCAUUGUAAAUUAAAGGUUUUCUUUGAGGCUCUUGAAAGUGAUCCCAUUGCUUUCCUGUUUUAAAAAUAUUUUAUGCUCUUUAUUUCCACUUCUGUGAAUGUGAUAUUUCUAUUUUGUGAUUAUGUUACUGAAUAAACAAACUUGCUACAUAAAAUUCUUAGCAAUUAAAAAAAUUCUGAUUCUGCCAUUUUGUCUCAAAUGUAAUAUACCCUUUUAAUAUCAUAUGUUUACAUAUUUAUGAAUGAUUAAUCAUUUUUGUUUGCAUUAAACUUUAUGAAAUGUCAGAAAUGAUUUUACUCUAAUGAAACUCAAAUUUUGCCCAAAGUAGCAAUAUUCUUAAAGAUGUUGAAUUUUGACUGGUUGAAUUUUAUAUAGUAACACACAAGUCGUGAUCAUCAAUAUUAUUGCAGACCAGGACUCUGCUUAUAUGCCUUGCUAACAAAGAUUUCUUUCACAGAGGCUUUUCUCCUCUCAAGACUUAAAGUAAGAAUUACAUUUUAUUAAGUCAGUUAAAUGCACCAUGGCUUCAUAUAGUAAUAUAAAAAAACUCUUUGAAGUGAGAAAUAUUAUAUCCUAAAACCUCUAAACCACAAACAUUCAAUUGAAAGAGUUCUGUUGAAGGAUAAUGACAUACUGACUGCUUACAGACCAAGUUGCUUGCAUUUUGUAUGUUUAGCCCUCCUUUGCCACUGCUUUUAGAGCCUUGGAAGGCUAAGUGUGAUAGUAAUGCUAGCUCUAAUGCAUAUUUAAAGGAGACUGCCUCGCUUUUAGAAGACAUCUGGUCUGCUCUCUGCAUGAGGCACAGCAGUAAAGCUCUUUGAUUCCCAGAAUCAAGAACUCUCCCCUUCAGACUAUUACCGAAUGCAAGGUGGUUAAUUGAAGGCCACUAAUUGAUGCUCAAAUAGAAGGAUAUUGACUAUAUUGGAACAGAUGGAGUCUCUACUACAAAAGUCUUUGGGUAUUUGUUUCUUACAUAGAAAAUGCUAACAUGAAUAGAAAGAUACUGGUGCAAGACCAUUCCCGGGAAAGUAGACAUACUUACAUUUUUUUCCUUUUCUGCUCAUUUGAAUGAACUCAAUUUUAUGUUAAAUUGUUAUAUCAGAGUGACAAAUAAGUGCUAUGGCUUGAUAGAAGUGAAGCUCUUCACAUAUAUUCAAAAUACAUAUCACAAACUUUGGUAAAUAGGAUAGUAAUCUGAAGAACUUUUGCCCUUUUUACCCCAUUUACUGUAACUCUUGUUUCUAGGUAAUCGUUCUCUCUCAACAAACUUCUCAAGCGUCUGUGUAACAAGCCACAUGUUCUAACAAAUUGUCUCCAUCGCACUUCAACAGCCAGGUCCCUAUUUUUUAUAACGUAUUAACCUUAUUAUUUUCUUAUUAUUUUAAAAGAAUCUAUGCACAUUAGCAAAAUUUAAAAGAUAGAGAAAAAUAUAAACAGAAAAAAUUAUGUUUACUUCUACCACCCUAAAUCAACUAUUAUCAAUUUUAUACAUAUUUUACUCCAUCUUUUUUCAAAGUUUCUUACAUUUUCCAAUGUCAUUAAAAUUCUCUGUGAAUGUAAAUUUUAAAAACUGUACCUACUGUUUUUUGGAAAUCUGUAACAAGCUAUGUGUAAUCAUUCUUCUAAUAUUAAACAUAUUGUGUCCAGAA